AGUCAGUAGCUCGCAGUGGAGGGAGGAGGAGCUCCAACUGUGCUCUUUGAUGGCAGUUUUUGCACCUUUGGGUGCUUGUCAUGUUCGUUUAUUUUUCAAAGAAGACAGCAGGUCCCUGACCUCAUAGACCAGCUAGUUUGGGAGGUGGCGGCAGAAUAAGGGCUGAGGACCCAGAUCUGCCUGGGGUCAGGCUGCUUCUAAAAGUGCAGGGCCACCCUCAGUAGUGUGGCUGCUAGGGCAGCACAGUUACAAUUUCGCUGAAGGCUGAGGCAGGAGUGGAGAGGCAUGGAGAGGCCCCAUGGGGAAUAUACUGACCUGUUGUAUCAACUCCCACUGUGGCUGGCCCAGGGGGAAGGACGCACCCUGUUAUGAAUCUGAUACUGAUAUUUAUGAGACUGUGGCUGCUGCAACAUCAGAAUCCACUACUGUAGAGCCUGGCAAGCUGGAUGUGGGAGCCACGGAGGGCCAAGACCUGCAGCACAUCAGCAACCAAAAGAUGCCCACAGGUCCCCCUGAGGACCGCCUGAGUUUAAAAUUUCUGCCAUCAAGUGAGGAAGACAAUGAUGAUGCCAAGAUUUUACCAUCACCUGUCCAGGGUUCUUCUGAGGACAACCUGAGUUUAGUAUGCCUACCACGAAGUGAAGAUGAUGACUGUGAUGAUGAUGAUGAUGAUGAUGCCCAGAUUUUACCGUCACGUGUCCAGGGUGGCUGUUACCGGUUUGAUAGCAGUUCUUGUUCUUCUGAGGACAACCUGAGUUUAGUAUGCCUACCACGAAGUGAAGAUGAUGACUGUGAUGAUGAUGAUGAUGAUGCCCAGAUUUUACCGUCACCUGUCCAGGCUUGUUCUGAAGAUAGCCUGUUUUUAAGAUGCUCACUGAGACACAAAGAUGAAGAAGAAGAAGAUGAUGAUGACAUCCACAUAACAGCUCGGAUAGAAAGUGACUUGACGCUGGAGAGUCUAAGUGAUGAAGAGAUUCAUCCAGCAUCCCACAACCAUGGCUGGCAGAUGCCAAGGGGAUGUGUGAGAUGGCCCAGCUCCAGGAUGAAACUCAACUUUAGGGAAGCUGGGGAGAGCCUCACAGCGCUGGACAAGCCAUCAGAUGGCACUGCCCCCAGGGACACACCCGGGGGCGUGGACAGGGAUAUGGAGGACCUAAGGCAAAGGGUGGCUUCAAACGUGACAGCAGAUCAGCCGCUGGGGAAAUACCAGAGGGGAUUUGACAGCUGGGCCAGGUGUUCCAGGACAGCACUUUCCAAAAGAUUUUCCAUCCAAACUUCCAGCAAGAAGUAGAUCUUCCAUCGUUAUCCAGAGCAUAUCUACGCAUUCAGGUAACUGAAGCAACAUUCCAGGAACCCUCACCAUCCCUCCCGUUGAACAGUUCGCUCUCCAGCUGGAGUCAGCUCUGGGCUGCCUCACUUUAACAAAAUGCUGGUUGCAGCCAUUGGAAUUAAUUUUACACCCUCUGAGUUGCAGUGCAAAAUUUGAAGACUGGCAUUUGGAAGCUCAGUAUCAUCAAGGAUUCAUUUAUUUUAUGAUGGUUGACAACAUUUUCCAGGCCACACUAACUGGGUCAGCUGGUAAUAAUAAUAAUAUGAUAAUUGGCCGGGCACGAUGGCUCACGCCUGUAAUCCCAGCUCUUUGGGAGGCUGAGGUGGGCUGAUCGCCUGAGAUCAGGAGUUCGGGACCAGCCUGAUCAACAUGGUGAAACCCCGUCUCUACUAGAAACACAAAAAUUUAGCAUGAUGGCGGGCACCUGUAGACCAGCUGCCUGGGAGGCUGAAGCAGGAGAAUUGCUCGAACCCGGGAGGCAGAGGCCACAGUGAGCCGAGAUAGCACCAUUGCACUUCAGCCUGGGCAGCAGAGUGAAACUCCAUCUCAAAAUAAUAAUAAUAAUAAUAAUAAUAAGCCCCUGAAGGUAUUACACAUGCAGCACUUUCCAGUUUAAAAAGGACUUUCAAAGGACAAGUAGUGUAUGGUCCCAUCCAUAGGAGGUAUCCAGAGUACCCAAAUAUAGAGAUGGGAACUAGCAUGGUGGGUGCCAGGGGCUGGGGGAGGGAGGAAUGGGAAGUUGGUGUUGAAUGGGGACAGAAUUUGAGUUCUGCAAGAUGAAAAAGAUCUAGACAUGCCAUUGCACUCCAGCCUGGGCAACAGAGUGAGACUCCGUCUCAAAAAAAAAAAAGAAAAAGCCAGUUGCGGUGGCUCACGCCUGUAAACCCAGCACUUUGGGAGGCCGAGGCAGGUGGAUCAUGAGGUCAGGAGUUUGAGACCAGCCUGACCAACAUGCUGAAACCCCAUCUCUACUAAUAAUACAAAAAUUAGCUGGCAUGGUGGUGGGCGCCUGUAAUCCCAGCUACUCAGGAGGCUGAGACAGGAGAAUCGCUUGAACCCGGGAGAAAGAGAUUGCCAUGAGCUAAGAUUGCGCCACUGCACUCCAGCCUGGGCAACAGAGCAAGACUCUGAAAAAAGAAAAAUCUAGAAAUGGAUGGUGGUGAUGGUUGCACGACAUUGUGAAUGUAGUUAAUGCCACUGAACUGUGUACUUAAAAAUGGUCAAGAUGGGCCAGGCGCGGUGGCUCACACCUGUGAUCCCAGCACUUUGGGAGGCCCAGGCGGGUGGAUCAUGAGGUUAGGAGAUCGAGACCAGCCUGGCCAACAUGGUGAACCCCAUCUCUACUAAAAAUACAAAAAUUAGCUUGUCGUGGUGGUGCAUGCCUGUAAUCCCAGCUACUCAGGAGGCUGAGGCAGGAGAAUCGCUUGAACCAGGGAUUCGGAGGUUUCAGUGAGCUGAGAUCACGCCACACUGCACUCCAGCCUGGCGACACAGCAAGACUCUCAAAAAAAAAAAAAAGGUCAAGAUGAUAAAUUUUAGGUUGUGUGUAUGUUACUGCUUUUUCACAGAUGAAGAAAACAACACUGACAUGCAUUAUCUCCCAACACCAACCUCAACCCAGCCCUGGAGUGUGAGCAGAGCCAGCAGCAUUUCCAGCCCCGCCUCUGGAGGAAGGAGAGGAACCUGAGACUCUUGGGUGACCUGAGGCGUCUCUGGCAGCACCAGCAAAAGAGCCUGGCCCUGGCCGCCCAGCACAGGUGCUCAGUCCCUCCUGACUGCCACUGCUCCCUCAACACCAAAGCACAGGGUCGCGAGAUGUUGGGAGAGGGUCGGGGAUGCUGGGCUGGGAGAGGACCGGGGGCCUGUCAGAAGCCAUGACAUGAUGCACUCACCGCUCAGGAGGAAGCUACUGGCCUUUGAGUGAAAUCUAUAAGAAUGAACUCUGGAGAUGUAUCGUACAACAUGGAGUCUACAGUUAAAAACUGUAUUGUAUACUGGAAAAUUGCUAAGAUUAGAUCUUCCAUGUUCUCACUACAAAAGCAUAAGUAUGUGAGAUGACGGACGUGUGUGUCAGCUUGAUUUAAUCAUUUUGCAGUGUGGCAAAGCAUCGCACUGUAGGUGGUAAAUAUAUAUACAGUUUUGUCAAUUAUACCUUCAGGAAGCUGGGGUGGUUGGUGUGUGUGUGUGUGUCUGUGUGAUGUGAGGUCAGUGAGGUGCUGAACAUGGUGCAUUAAACAGCAUUUUCAUUCUUA